AGCUACGUGGUGGCUCGCCUCUGAUUCCCCGUGUAAAAAAUGGAGUUUAGGAUCCCUGCCCUGUGUGCAGCCCACAGCCUCAAGCCCCCAUGGGGAUGGAAUGCCGGAAACCUCUGGCCAGCGCACUAGCAGCCUGGAGAAUACGGAAGAUUGUGGCAGGAUUGUGGGGCACAUGGGCAGCUCCCUGCUCGUCCGGGCCCCUGGUGCCCACGAGAAAACCAAAACAGGUGCGUGCCCCGCGCCGCACGUCAGGAGGGCAAGACUCAGUGGAGGGAGGGGCUGUCCACUCGCUCUAGCUCCCCAGAGGCUGAACAGGGAGAACUGGGAAAAAGGACGCCUCCUCAGCGUCCUAGAACGAGUCCUCGGCACCUGGUAUUGCAUGCGCCCUAGUAUGGGGCCGCUCCACUUGCGCAGGUGUUGGCAACAUGCGGGGAGCGCCACGGCAUGCCCCCAAUGAGCCGACUCCCUCCCCCAACUCUGCCCCCUUUGUCUCGCUGGCCCCUACUCCUUCUGUCUGCCUGUCUGUCCCGUCCCAGGUUCAGCGCGCACGGCCCUGCCGGGGUCCCUCUGGCAGUUGCCGUAGCCGCGCGGCCCGACCCGGGGCUCCCAAGAGGAGAAAAAAUCAUGAAUGAAAUGGAUGCGCUGCUCCCACUCCUCCGCCCUCCUUGUCCAAGCAACCUUGGCAUGGGGGCGACGACUGCGGAGACUCCGCGCAGAGUUGCUCGGGAGAGGGAGGCACCUGAGAUGAGGUCAGGGGUUAAGGGUCUGUGAUCCGGCCCCCUUCGUGCCCCGGGAGCAGGCCGCUCUCCCGGUCCCCCGCCCCGCCAGCCCUGCGCAAUUCCCGGCGAGCGGCGGAAGCCCGCCCGGGGGCGGGGCGGAGCCGGGGCUGGGGGGUGCCAAACCCACCCGGCGGCUGCGCCAGCGACUCUGCAGCUGAAGCGCAUUUGGUGAGGCGGUCGGGCGAGGGAGCGCGCACGGAGCGCGGGACGGAGCGCCAGGCGGACGGACCGAAGGACGGAGGCACCGAAGGACGGACGCCCCCGCACACGCAGACGCACAGAGCUCGGCGCGGCCCCCGUCGCAUACACACUGGCACAGACACAAGCAGGGACACACGCAGACACACGCACACUCGCGCGCGCAUCCUCCCGCCAGCCUGCCCGCCUGCUCGCCGGCGCCCGGAGCCCGCUCUGGCCGCUUGCUUUUUGCUGAGAAAGCUUCCUGCCCUGGAAGAUGGCACCCUUCCCCAUCCAGACACCUUGGGAAUGAAUUAUGAGGGAGCCAGGAGUGAGAGAGAGAACCACGCUGCUGAUGACUCCGAGGGAGGGGCCCUGGACAUGUGCUGCAGUGAGAGGCUACCGGGUCUCCCCCAGCCGAUAGUGAUGGAGGCACUGGACGAGGCUGAAGGGCUCCAGGACUCACAGAGAGAGAUGCCGCCACCCCCUCCUCCCUCGCCGCCCUCAGAUCCAGCUCAGAAGCCACCACCUCGAGGCGCUGGGAGCCACUCCCUCACUGUCAGGAGCAGCCUGUGCCUGUUCGCUGCCUCACAGUUCCUGCUGGAACCCACGGCCUGGCUUGACUCUGGGACGUGGGGAGUCCCCAGUCUGCUGCUGGUCUUUCUGUCCGUGGGCCUGGUCCUCGUUACCACCCUGGUGUGGCACCUCCUGAGGACACCCCCAGAGCCACCCACCCCACUGCCCCCUGAGGACAGGCGCCAGUCAGUGAGCCGCCAGCCCUCCUUCACCUACUCAGAGUGGAUGGAGGAGAAGAUCGAGGAUGACUUCCUGGACCUCGACCCGGUGCCCGAGACUCCUGUGUUUGAUUGUGUGAUGGACAUCAAGCCUGAGGCUGACCCCACCUCACUCACCGUCAAGUCCAUGGGUCUGCAGGAGAGGAGGGGUUCCAAUGUCUCCCUGACCCUGGACAUGUGCACUCCGGGCUGCAACGAGGAGGGCUUUGGCUAUCUCAUGUCCCCACGUGAGGAGUCCGCCCGCGAGUACCUGCUCAGCGCCUCCCGUGUCCUCCAAGCAGAAGAGCUUCAUGAAAAGGCCCUGGACCCUUUCCUGCUGCAGGCGGAAUUCUUUGAAAUCCCCAUGAACUUUGUGGAUCCGAAAGAGUACGACAUCCCUGGGCUGGUGCGGAAGAACCGGUACAAAACCAUACUUCCCAACCCUCACAGCAGAGUGUGUCUGACCUCACCAGACCCUGACGACCCUCUGAGUUCCUACAUCAAUGCCAACUACAUCCGGGGCUAUGGUGGGGAGGAGAAGGUGUACAUCGCCACUCAGGGACCCAUCGUCAGCACGGUCGCCGACUUCUGGCGCAUGGUGUGGCAGGAGCACACGCCCAUCAUUGUCAUGAUCACCAACAUCGAGGAGAUGAACGAGAAAUGCACCGAGUAUUGGCCGGAGGAGCAGGUGGCGUACGACGGUGUUGAGAUCACUGUGCAGAAAGUCAUUCACACGGAGGAUUACCGGCUGCGACUCAUCUCCCUCAAGAGUGGGACUGAGGAGCGAGGCCUGAAGCAUUACUGGUUCACAUCCUGGCCCGACCAGAAGACCCCAGACCGGGCCCCCCCACUCCUGCACCUGGUGCGGGAGGUGGAGGAGGCAGCCCAGCAGGAGGGGCCCCACUGUGCCCCCAUCAUCGUCCACUGCAGUGCAGGGAUUGGGAGGACCGGCUGCUUCAUUGCCACCAGCAUCUGCUGCCAGCAGCUGCGGCAGGAGGGUGUGGUGGACAUCCUGAAGACCACGUGCCAGCUCCGUCAGGACAGGGGCGGCAUGAUCCAGACAUGCGAGCAGUACCAGUUUGUGCACCACGUCAUGAGCCUCUACGAAAAGCAGCUGUCCCACCAGUCCCCAGAAUGACUGCGCUUCUCCUACAAGGUUCUCUGGGCACUGCCCAGCCUGAGUCUCGGCCCUCACCCAGGGCCCUGCCUCGGGUCCUGGGCCUGCUCCCCGCUUCCUCCCCUUCAGUCAGCUCCCUCUGUCCUCUGUCAGCCUGGCCUGACCCCUACCCUCCAGCAUUGCUCUUCCUACUGUACAUAUUGGGGAGUGGGGGGCAGGGUCGGGAAGGGACAUGCCAGGCCAGGCCUGGGGCCCCGGGGCCUGACCCACACCACGCAGACCCCGGGCUCCAGUUUUUAACGAUGGUUCCAUCAAUACCUGAUCCAGAAUGUUUCCGUGCUACACUUUGUGUCCUGCUGCAAUGUGUUCUGUCUGUCCAUCCAUCUCUGCCCUCUGUACCGGACACUGUGUCUCCUCAGCCAGGAAGGGGUAAUGAGCUCCAGCCCCUAAGCAACCGGACUUGCCUGCCUCGGCCUCACCCGCACUUCUCCCAAAAGGCAGAUGACGGGGAGUUAGGCAUGGGGAGCUCCAGAAGGUCACCAGAGAGCUUUCAGCUGAGGGAGAGUUCUCUAGGUUGGAGUGGGCAUCACAGCCAGGGUGGCCUCUGGGUGUCAGAUGCUCUCAGGAGGGUGCCCAGCCUGUGAGGCACUGGCAAGGUAGGGGGCAGAUGGGGCAUGGAGAACCCAGAGGAUCUAGGCCCUGUUGGGGAGGGGAGGGGAGCUCAAGGUUUGGGUGGGGACUCAGCCCAGAUCUACGUGAGACAUUUUUCUGUGUCACUGUGGGAAAGCCUUCCCAGAAGUCUCACUGCGUGUUGCUCUGCGUGUGUUCCCAUGUCCAUGCGUGUGUUGAGAGCCCAUCAGGAGGGCAUGCAUGACUCUUUGGCAACAUGUAUUAUCUUGGAGCCACGUGUUUUUAUUGCUGACUUUAAAUAUUUAUCCCACGGCAGACAGAGACAUUUGGUGUCUUUUUAUAAUUCGCUCGUGGUCAUUGAAUAGAGCAAUAAACGGAGCAUUUUGAGCAAAACUAA